GAGCUCAUUUUGCAGCUCUCAAGCUUUUAUAGCAUGCUGUAAACAAUUGUCAAAGUUGUUUAUCAAGAAACAGAUAGAGUUGCAACUUGUUUCUAGUAAUAGAAACUUUUACACUGCAUUCAAUGCCUAACGUUGCAGAAACAGAAAGGUCAAAUGAUUCUGGAAAUGGUGAGCACAAAUCUGAGAGAAAGUCACCUGAAGAGAAUCUACAAGGUGCUGUAAAAUCUUUCUGCACAAGUGCCUCAGGAGCACCCUUGGGUCCCAAAGGAGAUGGUCAUUAUCCAUGGAGUUGUCCAGUGACUCAUACACGGGAAAAAAUUUAUGCCAUCUGUUCGGACUAUGCCUUUCUCAACCAGGCGACCUCAAUCUAUAAAACUCCAAAUCCAUCCCGCUCUCCUUGCCUCCCUGAUAGUACCUCUUUAUCUGCUGGAAAUAAUUCAUCAAGAUACAUUGGUAUCCCGACUAGUACAUCGGAAAUUAUCUACAAUGAAGAAAAUAGCUUGGAAAACUUAUCCAACAGCCUGGGCAAGCUACCUCUCGCAUGGGAAAUUGAUAAAUCUGAAUUUGAUGGGGUGACCACAAAUUCGAAACACAAAUCAGGCAAUGCAAAGAAACAAGUUUCCAAGAGAAAAACUUCAGAUAAAAAGGGAAGAUAUCAGAAGGAAUGUCCUCAGCAUUCUCCUCUUGAAGAUAUUAAACAGCGGAAAGUAUUAGACCUCAGACGAUGGUACUGCAUAAGCCGACCACAGUAUAAGACUUCUUGUGGCAUCUCUUCAUUAAUUUCUUGUUGGAAUUUCUUAUACAGCACAAUGGGAGCUGGAAACCUUCCACCUAUUACCCAAGAAGAAGCUUUACAUAUUCUGGGCUUUCAACCUCCAUUUGAAGAUAUUAGGUUUGGUCCUUUCACGGGGAAUACAACACUUAUGAGGUGGUUUAGACAAAUUAAUGACCACUUCCAUGUAAAAGGAUGCUCUUAUGUUCUAUAUAAGCCUCAUGGGAAGAAUAAAACAGCAGGAGAAACUGCUUCAGGGGCCCUGUCAAAGUUAACCCGUGGAUUGAAAGAUGAAUCGCUGGCUUAUAUCUAUCAUUGCCAAAAUCAUUAUUUUUGUCCAAUUGGCUUCGAAGCAACCCCUGUUAAAGCUAAUAAAGCAUUCAGCAGGGGACCUCUCUCACCACAGGAAGUUGAAUAUUGGAUCUUAAUUGGAGAAUCAAGUAGAAAACAUCCUGCCAUUCACUGUAAAAAAUGGGCAGAUAUUGUUACUGAUCUAAACACUCAAAAUCCAGAAUACCUGGAUAUCCGGCACUUAGAGAGGGGACUGCAGUAUAGAAAAACAAAGAAGGUUGGGGGAAAUUUGCAUUGCAUCAUAGCAUUCCAGAGACUUAACUGGCAAAGAUUUGGCCUUUGGAACUUUCCAUUUGGAACCAUUAGACAAGAAUCACAACCUCCAACACAUGCCCAGGGAAUUGCCAAAUCUGAGAGUGAAGACAAUAUUUCCAAGAAGCAGCAUGGGCGUCUGGGCCGGUCUUUCAGUGCUAGUUUCCAUCAGGACUCGGCAUGGAAAAAGAUGUCUAAUAUUAGCAUUUGGUUAAACCAAGCACUUAAAGGAGUCCGGGAUCGCCAUGGGAACUCAAUAGAAAAUCCUCAUCUUCUCACUUUGUUUCAUCGGCUCUGCAAACUCUUAUUUUUUCGAAUUCGUCCUAUUUUUGUGUUUGAUGGGGAUGCUCCACUAUUGAAGAAACAGACUUUGGUGAAGAGAAGGCAGAGAAAGGACUUAGCGUCCAGUGACUCCAGGAAAACGACAGAGAAGCUUCUGAAAACAUUUUUGAAAAGACAAGCCAUCAAAACUGCCUUCAGAAGCAAAAGAGAUGAAGCACUACCCAGUCUUACCCAAGUUCGAAGAGAAAACGACCUCUAUGUUUUGCCUCCUUUACAAGAGGAAGAAAAACACAGUUCAGAAGAGGAAGAUGAAAAAGAAUGGCAAGAAAGAAUGAAUCAAAAACAAGCAUUACAGGAAGAGUUCUUUCAUAAUCCUCAAGCGAUAGAUAUUGAGUCUGAGGACUUCAGCAGCCUGCCCCCUGAAGUAAAGCAUGAAAUCUUGACUGAUAUGAAAGAGUUCACCAAGCGCAGAAGAACAUUAUUUGAAGCAAUGCCAGAGGAGUCUGAUGACUUUUCACAGUACCAACUCAAAGGCUUGCUUAAAAAGAACUAUCUGAACCAGCAUAUAGAACAUGUCCAAAAGGAAAUGAAUCAGCAACAUUCAGGACACAUCCGAAGGCAGUAUGAAGAUGAAGGGGGCUUUCUGAAGGAGGUAGAGUCAAGGAGAGUGGUCUCUGAAGACACUUCACAUUACAUCUUGAUAAAAGGUAUUCAAGCUAAGACAGUUGCAGAAGUGGAUUCAGAGUCUCUUCCUUCUUCCAGCAAAAUGCACGGCAUGUCUUUUGACGUGAAGUCAUCUCCAUGUGAAAAACUGAAGACAGAGAAAGAGCCUGAUGCUACCCCUCCUUCUCCAAGAACUUUACUAGCUAUGCAAGCUGCCCUGCUGGGAAGUAGCUCAGAAGAGGAGCUGGAGAGUGAAAAUCGAAGGCAGGCCCGUGGGAGGAACGCACCUGCUGCUGUAGACGAAGGCUCCAUAUCACCCCGGACUCUUUCAGCCAUUAAGAGAGCUCUUGACGAUGACGAAGAUGUAAAAGUGUGUGCUGGGGAUGAUGUGCAGACGGGAGGGCCAGGAGCAGAAGAAAUGCGUAUAAACAGCUCCACCGAGAACAGUGAUGAAGGACUUAAAGUGAGAGAUGGAAAAGGAAUACCGUUUACUGCAACACUUGCGUCAUCUAGUGUGAACUCUGCAGAGGAGCACGUAGCCAGCACUAAUGAGGGGAGAGAGCCCACAGACUCAGUUCCAAAAGAACAAAUGUCACUUGUUCACGUGGGGACUGAAGCCUUUCCGAUAAGUGAUGAGUCUAUGAUUAAGGACAGAAAAGAUCGGCUGCCUCUGGAGAGUGCAGUGGUUAGACAUAGUGACGCACCUGGGCUCCCGAAUGGAAGGGAACUGACACCGGCAUCUCCAACUUGUACAAAUUCUGUGUCAAAGAAUGAAACACAUGCUGAAGUGCUUGAGCAGCAGAACGAACUUUGCCCAUAUGAGAGUAAAUUCGAUUCUUCUCUUCUUUCAAGUGAUGAUGAAACAAAAUGUAAACCGAAUUCUGCUUCUGAAGUCAUUGGCCCUGUCAGUUUGCAAGAAACAAGUAGCAUAGUAAGUGUCCCUUCAGAGGCAGUAGAUAAUGUGGAAAAUGUGGUGUCAUUUAAUGCUAAAGAGCAUGAGAAUUUUCUGGAAACCAUCCAAGAACAGCAGACCACUGAAUCUGCAGGCCAGGAUUUAAUUUCCAUUCCAAAGGCCGUGGAACCAAUGGAAAUUGACUCGGAAGAAAGUGAAUCUGAUGGAAGUUUCAUUGAAGUGCAAAGUGUGAUUAGUGAUGAGGAACUUCAAGCAGAAUUCCCUGAAACUUCCAAACCUCCCUCAGAACAAGGCGAAGAGGAACUGGUAGGAACUAGGGAGGGAGAAGCCCCUGCUGAGUCCGAGAGCCUCCUGAGGGACAACUCUGAGAGGGACGACGUGGAUGGUGAGCCACAGGAAGCUGAGAAAGAUGCGGAAGAUUCGCUCCAUGAAUGGCAAGAUAUUAAUUUGGAGGAGUUGGAAACUCUGGAGAGCAACCUCUUAGCACAGCAGAAUUCACUGAAAGCUCAAAAACAGCAGCAAGAACGGAUCGCUGCUACUGUCACCGGACAGAUGUUCCUGGAAAGCCAGGAACUCCUGCGCCUGUUCGGCAUUCCCUACAUCCAGGCUCCCAUGGAAGCAGAGGCGCAGUGCGCCAUCCUGGACCUGACUGAUCAGACUUCCGGAACCAUCACUGAUGACAGUGAUAUCUGGCUGUUUGGAGCGCGGCAUGUCUAUAGAAACUUUUUUAAUAAAAACAAGUUUGUAGAAUAUUAUCAAUAUGUGGACUUUCACAAUCAAUUGGGAUUGGACCGGAAUAAGUUAAUAAAUUUGGCUUAUUUGCUUGGAAGUGAUUAUACCGAAGGAAUACCAACUGUGGGUUGUGUAACCGCCAUGGAAAUUCUCAAUGAAUUCCCUGGGCAUGGCCUGGAACCUCUCCUAAAAUUCUCAGAAUGGUGGCAUGAAGCUCAAAAAAAUCCAAAGAUAAGACCUAAUCCUCAUGACACCAAAGUGAAAAAAAAAUUACGGACAUUGCAACUCACCCCUGGCUUUCCUAACCCAGCUGUUGCCGAGGCCUACCUCAAACCCGUGGUGGAUGACUCGAAGGGAUCCUUUCUGUGGGGGAAACCUGAUCUCGACAAAAUUAGAGAAUUUUGUCAGCGGUAUUUCGGCUGGAACAGAACGAAGACAGAUGAAUCUCUGUUUCCUGUAUUAAAGCAACUCGAUGCCCAGCAGACACAGCUCCGAAUUGAUUCCUUCUUUAGAUUAGCACAACAGGAGAAAGAAGAUGCUAAACGUAUUAAGAGCCAGAGACUAAACAGAGCUGUGACAUGUAUGCUAAGGAAAGAGAAAGAAGCAGCAGCCAGCGAAAUAGAAGCAGUUUCUGUUGCCAUGGAGAAAGAAUUUGAGCUACUUGAUAAGGCAAAAGGAAAAACCCAGAAGAGAGGCAUAACAAAUACCUUAGAAGAGUCAUCAAGCCUGAAAAGAAAGAGGCUUUCAGAUUCUAAAGGAAAGAAUACAUGCGGUGGAUUUUUGGGGGAGACCUGCCUCUCAGAAUCAUCUGAUGGAUCUUCAAGUGAAGAUGCUGAAAGUUCAUCUUUAAUGAAUGUACAAAGGAGAACAGCUGCGAAAGAGCCAAAAACCAGUGCUUCAGAUUCGCAGAACUCAGUGAAGGAAGCUCCCGUGAAGAAUGGAGGUGCGACCACCAGCAGCUCUAGUGAUAGUGAUGACGAUGGAGGGAAAGAGAAGAUGGUCCUCGUGACCGCCAGAUCUGUGUUUGGGAAGAAAAGAAGGAAACUAAGACGUGCGAGGGGAAGAAAAAGGAAAACCUAAUUAAAAAAUAUGUAUCCUCUAUAAUUAGUUAUGACAGCCAUUUGUAAUGAAUUUGUCGCAAAGACGUAAUAAAAUUAACUGGUGGCACGGUC